ACACCAGGUGACUUCCUCCAACCCAGACUCGGCCAUGUCUUUCUUCUGACAGAAAACUUGCGGAGUUUCCUCAACACCAGUCAAUGCUCCAACCCCAACGGGGUGUCCAGCAACUCACUAACGACACCACCCAGAGUCAGCGCUGACCCCACAAGCUCAGCACUCUUCCCGCAGCUGCUCUCCUGCAGACGCCAGUCCCUGCCUCUGGACACCCGUCUUCAUUUCUGAACCCCUGCCUACAAACCAGGGACGCCCACACCCUCCUCAAGUUCAAUAAUGUGGCAGAACUACUCACAGAACUAAGAGAAGCGCUGUGCGCACCGACACCAGCGUAUUCUAAAAGAUGCGAACAGACACCAGCGUAUUCAGGAACAGCCACGCGGAGGAGGCGCACAGGGCAAGGGGACUGGCGGCAAAGUUGGCGCAGGCAGGUGAUUUGCUUCGCUUCCUCACACACCUCACAAAAGCCUUUCCUUCAAGACCCGCUGGCAGUCCCCAAACCACGAGCCACGGCAGAGCUUUCCCAUUAAUAAGUCCUGUUUGCUCACAUGAACUCCAUGUUUUGAUGGGGCCUCAAUCUCAUUCUGAACAGGGUAAAGUAGGGACGGGAUUCCGGACCACAGCUCCUCCCACGCCGGCACCGCGCAGGCCGCCGCGGUGUCUUCCGGAUGAGCUCCUACUCACUCCACAGCCCGGGGAAAGUGCAGGGCUACCGGCGCAGAGCUGCACAAGGAGGGCUGCAGGCUGGGCCAGAGCCGCUGUACGGGGACUGACAAGAGCGCGGGUCCCUCACCGGAGGGGACUGAGGACAGAGGGCUGAGCGGGAACUCCAUUCACAGACUCCUCCCACCGCCGCCAUUUCCCGCCGGUUCCGAUGAGGCCUCCACAGCCUUGGGACGCCCUGCCCUGCACACUCACCAUUUCCCGACUUCAGGAGUGUCCCAGAGUCUUAGAUACGAAUCAUCCAAUACCGGCAGGUCACAGAGCCACAGAGGCUGAGGCUGUGGCAGAAUCACCGAGGCUUCCCUAAGGAGCGGGAGCAGAGCGAUGAGGCCCUAACCGAGCUCUGGCUGGAGCUACAAGCAAAAGCCGCGCCAGAUCCCGGAUGCCGCACCCUCCUCUCUGCUGCGCGCCUCAUUCGGCAGUUGUCAAUCCAGCGCUCUAAUUGGAUAGAGCUGUAAGUCUCCCGCCUCAGGCCUUGAGUGACAGAAGUUGCAACCAUACACAGCACUGAAUGAGGCGAGAGUGACAGGCUCUGGCCUCCUGGUACUUUGAGGCAGGUUUUUUGUGUUUGUUUUUUGAGUCUGGCUCUUCUCGCCCAGGCUGGAGUGCAGUGGCGCGAACUCGGCUCUCUGCAACCUCUGCCUCCCGGGUUUAAGCGAUUCUCCUCAGCCUCCCAAGUAGCUGGGAUUACAGGUGCCCACCACCACACCCGGCCAAUUUCUGUAUUUUUAGCAGAGACAGGGUUUCACCAUGUUGGCCAGGCUGGUCUUGAACUCCUGACCUCAGGGUAUCUGUUCGCCUAUGUCUCCCAAAAUGCUGGGAUUAAAGGCGUGAGCCACCACGCCCGGCCCAGGCUGGGGUGUUAUCUCUGUGCUUGGCUUGGUACAGCCCAGUGGUCAUUUUUUUAACCUUGUGGUAUGUAAGGUUAGGUCCAUUUAUAAUAUAAAUUAUACACACACGCAUGCAUGCACGCACAUGCACACACACGUACACAUGCACGCGUGCAUACACAAACUUGUUCACAAACGGAAACAAUAUAAUGACAAUUAUUUUAAUGUUUUAUAACCUUUCUGGCCUCUGGUCUUUUGAGUAGGACACAUGAGAUUUUAAGAAGGAAGUAAUCCUCUAAAAAAUAAAAUGUUAGCUAUUAGUGAAUUUUCAAUUUUUUAUUAGCCACAUCGAAAAUAAUAAAAACAAGUGAGAUUGUUUGUGAUAAUUUUAGCCUACUAUAUCCAAAAUAUUAUUGUUUUAAUAUGUGAUCAAUAUAUAAUUGAGAGGUGAAGCCAGCUGGACUUCCUGGGUAAACUGGGGACUUGGAGAACUUUCCUGUCUUACAAGAGGAUUGUAAAAUGUACCAAUCAGCACUCUGUAAAAACGCACCAAUCAGUGCUCUGUAGCUAGCAAGGGGAUUGUAAAAUGCACCAAUCAGCACUCUGUAAAAUGCACCAAUCAGCAGGAUCCUAAAAGUAGCCAAUUGCAGGGAGGAUUGAAAAAAGGGCACUGUGAUAGGACAAAAACGGAACACGGGAGGGCACAAUUAAGGGGAAAUGGGAGGUGGAAUAAAAGCUGACCACCCCAGCCAGCAGUGGCAACCAACUGGGGUCCCCUUCGAUGCUGUGGAAGCUUUGUUAUUUCCCUCUUCAAAAUAAACCUUGCUACUGCUCA